AUUCCCCGCACCCACCCACGUCUUCCCGGGAGUCGUAUCCCGAGCAUGGAGGUUACUGAGACCGUUAUUUCUUCAUGGCCUGCCUAGCUUAAGCAGUAGCUGGAAAAGAAACGGAAACAGAGAGACAAAGUUUGACGAAGACCCGGAGUGGAGCAGCGAUUCAGACCCGGCACAACCGACUCCGUUGCCUUCCCCUAUGCCGCCCCCAACGCCACCGCCUCCCUGACUGCCCUGCCGUGCAGCGCCCGAUUCAGACUGGUUGUUAGAAAUCUACGCCAGAAUCUUUACGUGUGUCCAGAAAGGAAAGGAAUCAACAUUUCGCAUCAGCCUUCCCAAGAUGGCAGCUGCUGAAGACGAGUUCCUGCCGCCGCCGCGGCUCCCCGAGCUGUUCGAUUCCAGCAAACAGCUUCUGGACGAAGUCGAAGGAGCGACUGAACCCACCGGUUCCCGAAUAGUCCAGGAAAAGGUGUUCAAGGGCCUCGACCUCCUUGACAAGGUUGCCAAAAUGUUAUCGCAGCUUGACUUGUUCAGCCGAAAUGAAGAUUUGGAGGAGAUUACUUCCACCGACCUGAAGUACCUGAUGGUGCCAGCGUUUCAAGGAGCCCUCACCAUGAAACAAGUCAACCCCCGUAAGCGUCUAGAUCAUUUGCAGCAGGCUCGCGAACACUUUAUAAAAUACUUAACUCAGUGCCAUUACUAUCGUGUGGCCGAGUUUGAGCUGCCCCAAACCAAGACCAACUCAGCUGAAAAUCACGGUGCUAUUACCUCCACGGCUUAUCCUAGCCUCGUUGCUAUGGCAUCUCAAAGACAGGCUAAAAUAGAGCGAUACAAGCAGAAGAAGGUGUUGGAGCAUAAGUUGUCUACAAUGAAAUCUGCUGUGGAAAGUGGUCAAGCAGAUAAUGAGCGUGUUCGUGAAUAUUAUCUUCUUCACCUUCAGAGGUGGAUUGAUAUCAGCUUAGAAGAGAUUGAGAGCAUUGAUCAGGAAAUAAAGAUCCUGGGAGAGAAAGACUCUUCAAGAGAGGCAUCCACUUCUAACUCAUGUCACCAGAAGAGGCCUCCAAUGAAACCCUUCAUUCUCACUCGGAACAUGGCGCAAGCCAAAGUAUUUGGCGCUGGCUAUCCAAGUCUGGCUUCCAUGACAGUGAGUGACUGGUAUGAUCAACAUCAGAAACAUGGAGUGUUACCAGAUCAGGGAAUAGCCAAGGCAACACCAGAAGAAUUCAGAAAAGCCACUCAGCAACAGGAAGAUCAAGAAAAGGAGGAAGAGGAUGAUGAACAAACACUCCAAAGAGCUCGAGAGUGGGAUGACUGGAAGGACACCCACCCUAGGGGCUACGGCAACCGACAGAACAUGGGCUAAUCUUCCCACAACACCGCAGGACUGCAGGGUGCACACCUUCCCCGCCAAGGAAAACCAUGCAGCCUUCCCCUCCCUGAGCUCCCCUACAGCUGUGUAAAACGAAGGCAAAGAUGCUUAAUGUUGCUUUGAGUUCAAUAAAGUGUUAAAUUAUUA